CUCAUCAAGAAUUCCCAUGCAUUUUCUCGCUAUUGCAUUGUAAGGAAAAAGAUGCUAACGUUUAAAGUGGCUUUUACCUCCAAAGAUGUUUUGAAAUGUAUGUAAUUCUUUUGGCUAACUGUUCAUCUUAUGUGAAAUAUGCUUGGAAGAAGGCUUUAAAACUCGUGAUUAUAUAUACGGGUAUGCGUACAUAUCCAUACACACCACUGAAAAAUCUUAAAAUAGUUUUGUUACUCCUCUGCGUAUUAUAAUUACUCAGUAAAUUUAGUUUAGGUACAUUUAAGAUCUAAAGUACAGGACAAUUAUUUGUGUGAGAUUUUUACUGUGACACAUUUUAAAUACAUCGGUCUAACAAAUAGGGUUUUUUUGAAAUUAGAUAUUUUUAUUAACUCUUUAAAAAACGAAUCAUUCAUCUUGGGUUUAUAACUCUUUCAUCUGCCAUGUUGGAUAAAUUGCAAAAUUGGAUAAAUUGAUCUCAACUUAUCCAAUUAUCUUUGGAUAAAUUGAUCUCAACAUAAUUACCUAAUUGGUAGGAUGCCUUUGCAACGAUACUAACGUUAAUAAAAUGUUGAUGCUUUUAAAAAAUACUUAUGUUAAAAAAGCAUUUUCUCGUAUUUCUGGCAAGAAAAGUCAUGGAACUUUUUUCCUUCUAUCUGGAACAAGGUCAGCCAUAAAUAGUUUCUAAUACAUAGUGGGCACACAUUUGGUAACUAAGAUUAAUUAUAUCUACUGAAUUUACUGAAUUCCAUGUCCUUCAAGGGCAGUGACUAGGUGACUUUGUAUCUUCACACACCAAUGUUGCAGUAAAUGUUUGAGUCAGAUUGAAGUUUCAUCCCGGCUAGGUAGGUGCUAACUUAAUGACACCAGUUUCCACAUCUUCAGCUUUGAUGUUUCAACCUGCAGAAGGAUUUGGGCACGGAAGUGGCUGUGUCCUAAUUGUCUUCAAAUAUUUGAAGGUCUGUCAUGCAGCAAGGGAUUUCAUUUAUUUUGAGUAAUUAUUGAGUACAGAAAAACAGAUUUCACUUCUAUAUGAAGGCAAAAGUUGUUUAUGGUGAGAACUAGCGGUGGAAAGAAGGGGCUGCUCCUUCCCUAGGGGCUUUUGGGAUCAGCUGGUUCCCCACUUGGCGUGAAUGGCUAUUAGGAGGUAUCACAGAGGUAUAGGAGGGUCUUUCUGAGAGGGACUCCUGGGUAUUCCGAUGGCAACUAUAUUCGAGGACUUCUGUACUUCCCUUUUAGCACUGUGGCUUUUGUUUUUUGUUUUCUUAUGCUGGCUUCUAGAGUUGUGGACGUAGCAACAUCCGCAGACACCUACAUGAACCCUAGGAAGAUUUUUUAGUAGAUUAAAGACCCACCUGCUAUCGAAGAUGAUUCUUAGUCGUGCUUUGCAUUUGUAUGGCACAUUACAGGGAAUAAAGCACUCUCGAAUUCAAUGUGUUUUAAAAGACUCUUUUUAAUUAUACAUGAUUUGUAUUUCUUUCUUUAACUUUAUUUUCUACAAUAAACAUUGAAUCAAGAGGAAAAUUACCCUUUUCUAGGAAGGCAAGCAGAAAAGACUUUUUUUAAAGCUGUUUUUAAAAAAUGGGAUGGUGCCAGUCAUCCUUUGGAGAGCCAGCAAAUUAUGAAGGUGAAUCGUUCUUUUACUUGGCUGAAAACAUGUUUUAAAAGAUACUGAAUAAGGCCGGGGGCAGUGGCUCACUCCUGAGGCCGAGGCGGGCAGAUCACGAGGUCAAGAGAUCAAGACCAUCCUGAGCAACAUGGUGAAACCCCAUCUCUACUAAAAAUACAAAAAUUAGCUGGUCGUGGUGGCGCAGUAGUCCCAGCUACUCGGGAGGCUGAGGCAGGAGAAUCGCUUGAACCCAGGAGGCAGAGGUUGCAGUGAGCCCAGAUCACGCCACUGCACUCCAGCCUGGCAACAGAUGGAGACUCCGUCUCAAAAAAAAAAAAAAAAAAAAAAAAAACUGAAUAAGAGAUGAUAUAAGAGAUGAUUCUUGUGCUUGCUCCGCAUUUUAGUUUGUUUAUUUCAUUACUCAAACAUGACUCAAGUUUCACAGCAAAAAGUCCAGUCAUAUCCACCUACAUUAAGUUGCAUUGGAUGUUUUUUCAGUAUGUCUGCAUGGUUUUUAAAAUAUGCUGGCAGCUGAAGGUAAAACAAAGCCAAGAAGUAGAAUUACAGCAAGCCGAAAAGCUUAGGGGAAUUGGAGCUUUGUGUUUGAAGAAGAAAGACAUGUGCCCUAUUUGUAUGAAACCAAUCUUGAGAAUGAUGGUUUUAUCAGCAAUGGGAAUAAGGAUUUAUCUAUUAUAAUAAAGAUUCGGCUACUGAGUGUCAAUCUAAUACAUGUAUUAAGUGGGUCAAUGAGGUGGGGACUCCAGUCUGUGGCUAAGAAGCAGAGCAGAGUUGCCUGUGAACACCAGAGUGCCCAAUACACAAGGAUUGAAGUGCAGCAAGUCAGUAAUGAGGCCGAUUGAGUUAAACCAAGAUCUGACCUCUCCAUUUUAGGAAGAAGAGGAAAAAACAAUUCUGAAUUAAUGUUUGCAUGGACUUAACUUUUUAAAUGUCUUUUAAAGUAGUUACUCUCUCGUUCUCUAGCAGAUGAGUUUGUUUCAUGCUUUUAACUUUUUAAACGUCUUUUAAAAUAGUUACUCUGUCUUGUUCUCUAGCAGAUGAGUUUGUCUCAUGCUUUUCACUUUUUAAAUGUCUUUUAAAAUAGUUACUCUCUCUCAUUCUGUAGCAGAUGAGUUUGUGUCAUGCUUUUGUGUCUCUUACCCAUUAGCUGACUUUGGGUGUGAUAAGUGACUAAGACUCCUCAAACUUUGAACAAGGAAUAUACCAUUUAUUUAUGCUGUAUGCAUGAAGGGAAAAGAGACGAAUAUCAAGUUUUUCUGGCCAACCAAGAAAUAAAACUUUAAAAGUGUUUAUUUUUUCAGGAAAAAAAAUCACAGAUACUACUUAAAUAUUAUUACCAGGACAACAAAUUAGCAAAUAAGGCAAGUUAGAAAGCAGCAUUUUCAAGGUUAAAGGUUGCACUUUAAAGCUUUAACCAUGACUUCUGAAGGGAUCACACAAACAUCUUUAAAGACUUCUUUGUUAAUCAGAAAACAGUUUACAUGCAAAUUUCCACACUGGAGAGCCGACCGAGAUCAAUACUUUCAUGAUUAUUCCCAAUUUACUGCUUUAUCAGAAAGAACUUUACUACGAAGCAAGAAGUGUCUACUCUUCUGUGAAGGAGUAAGUUUUCUCCUUGUUUCUGAAAUUCUUUAUUCUAGCUGAAUUCUCAAGACUGAGCAGUGAACUUCCAUUGGUUAGCACCAAAUAGAGCAAGCCUGAGUAAGCUGCUUAUAAAAAGGGGAAAAAAACGACAGAAGAAAACUUUUAAUAAAUGGAAUAUGAGGCACAUAAUACUCUGCUUCUACAAAUUUUCUUUUUGUUGCCUCUUUGGCAACACUUAAGAUACUAAAUUUAGGUCUGCAUAAAAUCCAUUAUCCUUUGCUCUUCAGAUUUCCUCCCCAGUCCAUUUCUAAAUGCAUCCUGUGCCCUUCUCAUUUACUAUGCAGGUAAGAGAGUUUAUGAGAAGUCAUUAAAGCCCAUGUUCUUAGGUAACAUUGUUUAAGCAUUAAACACUACAUGUAAAUUGUCAUUCUCAAUAUUAUUACAAUACUGUCUUUCUUAAAGUUGCACAUUUUACCUAGAAAUCCGUGGCAUCAUACUCUGAAAAGAUCAUCUUCGAUAUAAUGCAGAGGACACGUAAAAACACUGGGUUCCCAAGAGAAAGUUCCAUCUCUGUCAUACAUAGCAUAAUUAUCUUAGGCUCUCCAUAUUUUUCUAAUGAUAAGUGAACGUAAGAGGUUAGGCUCGUGCCAUACCUUAAACAUUGAAGGAGGCUUUUUGUAACUCCUUUCUCUUCGGCUGUCACACACAUCAACCCAGAUGAAAGGCACUGCUAGUGUUUCUGCCUCGGUGGCUAGUAGCGUGGGAGAGCAGAUACACUUUUUAAAAAUAGCCAAAUCUUGCACAUUGAUAAGAAAGAUGGAGAAAGGUUGGAGUUUUUCGCUCAGUUUUGUGUUCCCAUAGAUAAGAACAUAGCAGAAGUUAUUAGGUUUGGCCUGUCAUUUUCAAGGAAGGUCAGUAUCUGAUACUGAGUCAUCUUUAUCUUCUGGUUGAGUCCCUAUGACAAGACCAGAACGUUCUAGUAGAAUAGAGCAGCAGCUUUCUGGCAUUAAGGUACUUGCUCAUUGACAUGCCCUAUUGCUCUCGGGGGAGGAAGGAUGUGUAAUCCUCCUCAGCCUCUGCAAUGUGAUUUCAAGUGAGGAAUUGCUUUCCAUCAAUAAAGCGGUCAAGUCAGUUUUUGACAAGUUUAUUAGUACAGUAAGACUGUGGUAUCAGGACCCAGUUCAGAGGUGAACAAAGCCAAACCAUAUUGUUUGAGGGCAAAGGCAGGUUUUUAGGGGAGAGACAAAAUAAAUAUCCAAGUAGAAACAAAGCUAGACUUGAGACCUUGGAGAUAGGUUGACAGCUGUCUAUUUGGAGGUUCUUGUGUCUCAUCCCUUUUUGCAGGAUGGAACUCAGAGCUUUGGAUGACGACUGGCUAAUUCUAGAACACUGCACUGAAUGUUACUCAUUAGCAGGCUGUGGUUAGAGCAGAGUGCCUUUCCAAGUAGUCUCAGGAUGCCAGCGGGACCUGCCUGUGCAGUGACCAUCUUGAGUCUGAAAUUUAAGUGGAAAGCAGCAAAUUAGCCAUUCCUGUGUUUAGAGGAAAACUGAGUUUAGUUAGAAGGUGUGAAGUCGUUGGGGCCAGCAUGUUCCUACUGAAGAAACUGGGAAUCCUCGGCAGGUUAGUAGCAAGCAGAACUUUAGAGUCCCUUGAAGGAAGGUUGAAGUGAUGUUUGGACUGCUGAACUGCAGAGUGAACCUGGGAAUGAGAUGCACUGACACCCUCAUCAGUGCUUUCCAUCAGUGUGCAAGACUUAGCUAUUUCUCAAAAGAACACAGCUUCCUCUCACAUGGAAUGUCCUACCAUUGGGGAUGUAACCAGAAGCCUCUGAAGCCUACUCAGUUUUUUAGGUGAAGAUCCCAGAUUUUUGUUUGUCACAACUCUCAUGGUUACAUUUAUAGGUAGGGAAUCCAGCCACUUCAGUCCAGUUUCUGAAAAUUCCUGGCUAGGUUAUUUUUCAGAGUUCCAUUUGGACAUUUUACCACCUCUUCUGAUUGUGGACAAGACAGUGAAGGCAUUGAUGAAUGUGUAGGGCUUUACAGCUUUAUUUACAAUCCAAUCUGGAAAUGAUGGACUCCUGUUACAAAUAGACACACUUAAUGUACCAAAUCUGGAAAUAAAAUAUUUCAGAAGUCUUUUUGACAGUCAUUGUGUUAGCCUUUGCAUGCAUCUUCUAUACCCAGUGAAAUUACUAAAGCAUUCACAUGAAAACCCAUUUUUUCUCAUUUGAAUAAAACUAAUGUGAAUAUGCUUAUAAAUGCCUGCCUCCCACCCUACAGCCCCAUCCGUAGAUAAGCUGCUCUCGUUGUCUUUAUGGCUACUUCCCACAACAUGAAUGGACGGGUCAAACAACUCACACAGUGCUGAUGAGCUACACUGGUAAAUUUGGAGCAUGCCACCCACAUAUGAUUUUCCCUGGCAUCCCUUCUUGUUGGUGUGUACCAGGCCAUGGGACACUGGAGCAAGAUGAAGGCACUUUGGAGCUACCAAGAGGCUCUCUGAAACCCUGACAGUCUUUAGAGUCCCUUCUACGAUGUGGGGCCUGAUCUAGGACAGGGACAGUGUGGGAAAGAGCCACCAUAAGGGACUGUUCAGUCUGAGAAAGAUGACUGACCAUAGAUAACCUUGACCGUGUUAUUCACCAAAGGAAGUAUAUUUCCAAAACAGCCCAACAUGGGUUACAUGAGGGCCGUGAGAAAUGUAAGCUCCUCCAAGAGCGUGCAGCCCUCACUGUUUUCACAAUUGUCCAUAGUCAAGACAGGAAAAAGUGAGAAAGAAAAGCAGGACUUCAUACUCCAGUGAGAGCGAUAAACUUUGACUUCUGGACAGAAUAUACAGAGGUCAAGAUGAAUCAAGAUUCCUCUUUAUUGAGAAGAGAUUGCAUCCCAAAGAUCAAUUUGCUUUUCUGUGAGUGGUUAGUCUUGUCUCCUCAGUUAUACACAAGUGUUUAUUGAUAGACCUCACUAUAUCUCGAUGCACACGUACAAGCACACACGUCAUUCCAAACAGUAUAUUUAACUGGCAAUAUAUUUAGCGAUUUAAAAUUGUAGUUUUCAAAUGUUAUCAAACAUAUCAGGUGUCCUAAUACGUCAAUUGAUUUUACCAUCAUAAUUUGAGCUUUAAGAACAAGUAUUUAAAAAAAAGACCCAGUAUUCAAAAAAAGACCCAGCAGCUCAUCCGUGGGGAUUGUCAGGUGACGAGAUGUUUUUUCCAUUUGAAUUUUAAUUUCUUUAUCAGUUUUUAGGUAAAUAUAAAUUAUUAACUAAUUGCCUCACUAUUCUGCUGGUACAAAGGGAAUUAGGAACUUUAGAAAACAAAAUUUACAUUAAAAAAUAAUGCAAUUGUUAUUUAAAAUUGGCAGAAAUGUGAUAUCUUGAAACAUUAUUCAGCUAAUGGAAGUAGAGUGACUCUUGGUUGUCAUAAUAUUGUCUGGAAUUUUUAAAAAGCAAUUUAUAAAGAUACUAGUUUCUUAAAUUACAGCUCCCUGUAAUUUGUAUACUCAGGUUUAGAUUCACCUACUCUGAAAUCAUGGUGGUAGGUAGUCAUUGAGCUGUUCUGUAAGGCAAGUGUCAAGAAUUUAGGAAGUUCCAUUUAAUUUAGCCUUUGUGAAAAAAUUCUACUUUUUGUAUGAAUUGUGUGCCCCACCCCCACUCCCAAAUAUUAGCUCCACAAAGGCAGAAUUUUUAUCUCUUCUAUUUGUUGGUGUGUUCUGAGUGUCCUCCACAGUGUCUGGCUCAAAGCUGCUUAAAGAUGCUUCCUUUAUGGAAAGAAUGAACUGUAAUAAUUUAUAUCACCCCCCCAUAUAGAAGACAUAACCUUCUCUUAUACCCCCAAAUUCACAAAAAUAGAUAUGAAAGGAUUUUCUUUAAAAGUACUAAGAACUUGAAUAAUUUAUGUAGUCUUCUGUGUUAUAUUGGAAUAGCCUCCUUGUUGUUAAUACAGACACUUUUUUUAAAAAAAAGAUAAAUAACUUUUCAGUUUGUACCUGUUACGUUUAAACUUUAUUUUUAAACUGCUUUUAUAACCUGAGCAAUUGUUUUUAUUUUGGGAGAGACCUUUUCCAAGUAGAAAACCAUUUUAAGAUUUACCAGCGCAGCACUAAUUACUUCAAUUUCUGUAGUAUAUUUCUGCAAAUUACAAAGUUCAAAUUAUGGCUCUUGUAAACAGGGUUUCCUGGUGACCAUGGAACCUGUACUUUCAUUUCUCCCGCCUGGAAAGCUUUCUUAAAGUGCUAGUAUAUAUAAAAUAUUAGGAGUUUUGACAUGAUUUCAUAAAUUUAUUGGGAGUCUAAAAUUCUUGUAAAGUUUACGUAUUUAGUGAAGUCCUUAAAAACAAAGCUCUUUGCAUUGAAGAAAUAUUAAAGCCUUUAAACAUCAAAGUUUCCUGGAGAUUUCCUGCCUGCAUUAGAUAGAGUACUCCUGUGGAAACUGCACACCUAGCUCAGCUGCAAUGUGUCCACUUAAUUUCUGUGGAAAUACGCAGCUUUAUAACCAUAACACUGGAGUCCCUAUUGCAUUCCAGAUUUAUCUUGCACUCACCCUCUUCACUUCUCAGGUCACUUUAGCGUUCAUAGAAGAAAAGCAAAAUCUCACAUUAUCAAGAAACAGGAAGAAAAUUACUACAUUCUUAGGCAAUUUGGAGUUUAUUUGCAAUCCUUUUUCUUCCAAGCAAAAGAAAGCAAGGAAAUGCUGAUCCAGUGUUCCAGUCAUUUUAGCUAAACAGGUUAAGUAGUCCCUUUCUGCACUCCUGCCUCGCUGAGCGUGUAAGAUACAAGGAAGAAACUCACUCAGAUAGGCUCCUAUUGUCCCCUCACCUGCUGGUUGCCUUUUUCUCCAGAGUUAGCAGCUGUCUGGUACGGGAGGGAUGCUGCAUGUGGUGAGAGUUUGCCCUCCCAAAAGUGCCAUACGCUGCGUUUACUAGCCAUCCCAGAAACCCAGAGAGAGCAGGAUAAACCUCAAGUCCAAAGAGGAGAAAAGGCCUGCCUUAAAUUAGAUUGACCCUAACCCUGGGGGUUUCUCAGCCAAAACUCUCUUGACCUUUGGGGCCAGAUUGCCCUUGUUGUGGGGCUGUCCUGUGCGUUAUGGUCUGUUUAGCAGCACCCCUGGCCCUGCCCACUAGAUGCUGGUGGCACCCACCCACACGCUCAUGACAGCCCAAAGCAUCUCCAGACAUCGCCAGAUGCCCCCUGGGGGCACAGCUGUCCCAGCUGAGAACCACUGCUCCAACUUGAUCAAACUCAAGAUUCAUCAGGAGAAUGAGAACCCCGUGUUCUUUCAUUAAUUCCGACUGCUUACAGUUUGCCUCAUAUCAGAAAACUUACACGCUAAUUCCAUCUGUUCUUUAGAUUUUUUAAAAAAAAACCUAUAUCUUGCAUCAGCCAUAAAACAAUGACUGUAGAUUCUCUGAGGGAAAAAAAAAACACCGUGUAGAUGGUGUUCUCAGCAGGUGAGAGUCAGACUGCAGAAGCAGGCCAGCUCCUCUGUAAGACCCACAUGAAGAUUACUGUUGCCACUGCCAGAUUAUGUUAUGUCUCACACAGAGUCGCCACCUUCCUCUCUCUACUCCCCAUCCUGUUCCGCCUUCUGAAUCGCAGCAUCAAUUGUUGACUUAAGCAGGCAAAAACUCAAACUACAUUUGAAUAAAGAAUUUGUCAGUAUCUGCAUUUGUUUUAGUCUUCUGUAUCAAGAGAGGAACCCCAAGCCCCUUAUCCAGCUAACCAGAACACCUUAAAAGUGUUUGUCUUCAAAAAAGAUAUCACAUGAAAUUGUAUUAUUAAUAAAUUAGUAAAUAAGGCAACCAAUUUAAAAAGCAAACAUUUAGAAGUUCAAAGCUGUAUUUUAAAGGAUUCAGCAACAAUCUAUAAAGCCCAGGUGUCUUAAAAUACUUGUUUGGUAAUAAAAACACAAUUGUACAUUUUUACAUGUUUCCACACAGAAUAGCAGAGUAAGCUUGUAGCUCUUUAAGAGAACUAGCUUUUUAACCCAGAAUAGUAUCUGUUUUUCUGCAGCUUUAGGAGAGAGGAAGCAUUUUCUCUUAUUCUGAUUUUUUUUUUCCACAAGCAGCAGCAUCAAGAAUAAGCACUGGAAUUAUAUUAGCAUCUGGCACGAAAGAGUAGACCUGAGAAGCUUACAGCUUAAAAUACGGGGAAAGAAAAGGGCAAAAGAGAAUGUUUAGCAAAUGGAAUAUUGGCCAAACGGUGUUCAGGCUGUGCGGGAUAUGCACUUUUAUAUUUUAGAGGGCUGCAGCAUUUCGUCUUCUUUUAGGGACAGUAUAUUAUCUAGUUGAGAGCAUAGGCUUUGGAGUCAGACUGGUUUGGGAUGACCCCACCUCUGCCACUUACUAGGUGUGACUUUAAGGAAGUCAUUUAACCCUCCAAGCUUAUUUGCCAACGUGUGAACUGAGGAUAAGAAUAUCUGCUCCUUAGAGUGUUGAUCAAGUACGUAGCAUGGCGCCUGGCACUGAGCCCUCAGUAAAAGGUGAUUCCAUGUUGAUUCUUCUCCUCUGAAGCUAAAGGCUGUGUCGCUACUGCAGUUUCUGUCUGCUUCACCCUGCAUCGUCCCUGCCGGACUAAACUCCCUUAAGUGGCGAUUUUGCCUCUAUUGAGUAAAAACUUAGCUUUUCCCCAUUGCUUAUCUUUUCCAUCUCGACUUUUCUGAGCAACUUUUAAUAUACAACUUAAAUCUGACACUAGCUUUUCUAUCUAACCUUAUUUUCCACCAUUCCCCAGAAUCAUCUUUCCAUAUCAGAUAGUUUAAUGGUCUCAUGUUCCUUCUAAAACUUAAUUCAUAUUUACUUCACCAGAAAUGCUUCCUCCUGUCCCAACUCUGCCCAUCCUUUGAGGCUCAGUUUAAUUCCAACCUCUUCAGAGUAAAACCUUUUUCACUCCAGUCCUUAUUCACUCAUUUAUUAGGUACCUCCAUGUGUCUGGCAACAGAUAGGUACCAGGAAUGCUACAAUAAUUGAGGCCGGCCCCUGUCUUCCAGGAUUUAUGCAGCCUGAUGCAGGAGAGACAGGUAGAUAAGAGAAGAGCUGCCAGUGCUAGGAUGGGCAGCCCUUCACCCUUCAUGGACAGCCUUCCCCUGGCUCCUGUACUUGGCGGAUGCCUCAUGAGGAUUUAAUUAUACAUUGUUUUCUUUGUACUUUAGUUGCUGAGUCUCAUAUCCCCAAGUAAAUUGUAAGCAUAGGACUGAGUACACAGUGAGCACUUUAGAAACAUAUGCUGGCUUGAUCUUUCACCUCCAGAUGCAUAUUUAAAAGGAGAAUCGAUUGCCUGGCCUAUUGUAAAGGCCUUGUAAACUUUAAAAAGCAAAUUAAAAAACAAAAUCAAUGAUGACGUUAAGCUCUUGGGGAUCCCCAUAACGUCCUGGUGAUUAGAGUGGCUAGGCGACUAGGCUUUGGAAUUCAUGGGACAGUGCACUUUUAAAUUUGGCAGUUCUAAAAUGAAAAUAAAGAAUUGUCCUUUGACUCUAAUAAAGUUAGCUUAAUGGAAAACUCACUGCAUUGUCCUCGUUUUUCUCACUGUGUCACAGACCAAGAAAAGCGUCAUCCAAGCUCAUGACAGGUGUUCCCUGAAUUUCUGAGCUGCUGAGUGCCACUGAGGAGCUCAGAAAGCAUGAUCUGAAUCGUGAGCUUACAUGCGACACGGCCACAUCUCAGCUUCAAUGCCAUGUCACAGGCUCAGCAUUGACAGUUCACAUACUUGGCUCAUAAGAUAAAUUUCCAGGUGUCAGUAAGCUGCACCAGAGAAGAUACUGUAUGUCACAAACUCCAGGAAGUCCUGAGCAAGCCCACAUUUUCCUUUCCACAGAAAUGAACAUUUUUAGGUGGCUUGAUAAUUUUUUACUCUUUUUAUUUGCGAGCUUUCCCAUUACGGCAAUCAGAGACAUUUUUCCAAGCCCUCUGAUGCUCACUAAUACAAGAUACAGCAUAGUACCUAAUGAUGGGGUUGGGGAGGGUGCUGAGUGAGAUCACCACUAAUGUGCAACUCCUAGAAAGAAGCCUUUCUUAAAGGGCCAGCCCAGGUUUCCAGAAGCACCAUUAUUGUAGGUGGCUGGGAAAUAGCAGGGAACAAGACAGAAAAGUCCUUGUUCUCCUGGAGUUUACAUGCUAGUAAGGUAAGAAAGAUAAAUAAGCGACCUACCUUUAGAUAGUGAUAAAUGCUACGAAGACAUAAAAUGGCAUGAUGAUGAUGGCAGUUGAAAAAAAUUGUUAAAUUAUUCCAGCAGUACAAGGUGAGCACUGGCCACGGCAGGUCCCAUGACAGUUUAUCUGGGAGCAAAUGAAACCUGUUUGGAUGACUCUCCAUAUUGAAGCAAUGAUAGUAAACACAUAGCUCUAGCCAUGGUUCUAAAUGCUUUAGAUCUGUGCUGCCCAACAUGGUAGACACUAGCCUCAUGGGGACAGUACAUUUUAAUUCCAACAAAAAAUGAAAAAUUUCUCAGACACAUGAGCCACAUUUCAGGUGUUCAAUAGCUACAUGUGGCCGCAACAGCUACAGAAGAGUGUGGUCACAUCUCUGAGCCUCAGUUCUUUAAAAACAGCAUAAUCAUACCUAUCUUGCUGAUUGUUUCAAGAAUUAAGUGAUCAUCUAUAAGCCUGGCACCUAAGGCCGCAUGCGGUGGCUCACACCUGUAAUCCCAGCACUUUGAGAGGCCAAGGCGGGCAGAUCAGUUGAGGUCAGGAGUUUGAAACCAGCCUGGCCAACAUGGUGAAACCUUGUCUCUACUAAAAAUACAAAAAUGAGCCGGGCGUGGUGGUGCACACUGGUAGUCCCAGCUACUCAGGAGACUGAGGCAGGAGAAUCGCUUAAACCCAGGAGGUCGAGGUUGCGAUUGCACCACUGCACUCCAGCCUGGUCAACAAAGUGAGACUCCAUCUCAAAAAAAAAAGCAAGCCUGGCAGUCAGACAUUUGGUGUGGCUGCUUUAUUGGACAACAGAGAAUAGAAUAUUUACAUCAUCACAGAAAGUUCCAUUGGACAGCAUCUGUUCAGAUAAACUCAAUCUUCCCCCACAUCCUAAUGAGGUGUAGAUACUGCUUUUCCAUUUUGCAGAUGAGGAAGUAAGGCACGGGAGUUACGUGUGACUUGCCCAAGGCUGCAUCCUUAACGAAGGGCAGAACUGGAAUGCAAACCGUGGAGGUCUGGAUCCAGAGCCUGGGGGUUAAUCCUACCCUGCUAUGCCGCUAUAGCUCGCGGAUCCAGUACAGCUCAUCUGUGUGAUCCACUUUCAACCAGAGUGCAACCGAGGGAGAGAACAUUACCUCUUCAGAAAAUCUUGUCAUUGAAUGCUUUUAAAGUCAGCUAACAUGAAUUCUGACGAGAGGAUCAGGAAAAAUGUAGGCCUGUCAUAGGCACAAUUUCCCCCUCCUUGAAAAGGGCAGAGGAAACUACAAAGCACCAAAAAAAUACCAAGUUUAUGUAUGAUCUCAAUAAGGCAGAUUAAGCUCUCUACGCCUCAGUUCCCCUAUCCUAGAGCGGUGUGAGGAUGUAAUGAGGCAAGGCCUGGAAAGCCUCAGCGGGACCUGCCACAGUCAGUGACGCCAGGGAGGUCAGCAGCAGCAUUACCACUGCACUCAAGCGGCCACACUUGGGCCAAACGUUCCAGAAUGCACAGGACACAGCAGAACAGACCACUUAUGUGAGGAGGCAGCUCGUCCUUCUCUCCCAGAGCUGCCAUGAGAGUCUGUGGUUCCAAACAGCCUGAGUUUGAAAUUGGAGAGCACUUCAGGAAGGCACGAGGCAGAGGAGGUGGCAGCCUUUGGAAAGAAUCUGCAUUUGGCUCAUGCAUUUAGGAUUUGCAAGUUUAGUUAAGUGUCUUCACUCAUCUGAGCCUCCAUUCUUUAAAAAAUGGGUUUAAUUGGCCGGGCGUGGUGGCUCAUGCCUGUAAUCCCAGCACUUUGGGAGGCCGAGGCAGGAGGAUCACCUGAGGUCGGGAGUUUGAAACCAGCCUGACCAACAUGGAGAAACCCCGUCUCUACUAAAAAUACAAAAUUAGCCGGGCAUGGUAUUGCAUGCCUGUCAUCCCUGCUACUCUGGAGGCUGAAGCAGGAGAAUCGCUUGAACUCGAGAGGCAGAGGUUGUGGUGAGCUGAGAUCACGCCGUUGCACUCCAGCCUGGGCAACAAGAGUGAAACUCUGUCUCUAAAAUAAAAUAAAAUAAAAAAUGAGUAUAAUCAUACCUACCUUGCAUGAUUGUUUUCAGAAUUAAGUAAUAGGCCGAGAGUGGUGGUUCACAUCUGUAAUCCCAGCACUUUCAGAGGCCGAGGUGGGCAGAUCACUUGAGGUCAGGAAUUCGAGACCAGCCAUGGCGAAACUCCGUGUCUACUAAAAAUACAAAAAUUAGCCAGGUGUGGUGGUGCAUGCCUGUAAUCCCAGCUACUCGGGGCUGAGGCACAAGAAUCACUUGAACGUGGGAGGUGGAGGUUGCAGUGAGCCAAGAUCACACCAUUGCACUCCAGCCUGGGCGACAAAGCGAGACCCCCCCAUCUCAAAAAAAAAAAAAAAAAAAAAAAAGAAGGAAAAAAAAAGAAUUAAGUGAUCAUCCGUAAGCCUGGUGCAUAGAAAUUUGGUAAAUAAUGGUCAUAAUUACUAUUUUGAUUAAUGAUUUUCAGCUUCUCAUUAACAAAUGUCCUUGAGUAUUUUCUUGCCCAGAUGCCUUAGACCCAGGGAAUGUGUUAGGACAGUUAUCCUCAAACAUGAUUGCUGUUACCACCCUUUACAGUGCAGUGAUCACACCCUUGAGAAGCCAGGCAGAACCAACUGAAAGGCAUCGUGGGGCGUGCACAUAGCAGCUGCUUGCAAAGAUGGAAGCUGCCUCACACUCCCCCACAACCAGCAAGGGCAGUGGCUGCCAGGUAUGACCUCAGGUGACCAUCCUGUGCAUUCUGAAAACUGGGAAGUCAAACUCUCCAGGCUCCUGACUGGCCAGUAGGCUUCACCAGAGCUGGAUCAACCAGAAGAAGCUGAAACAUCCAACCUAAGAAUUUCGAACUUCAAAUGGAAAAUCUGGGCACUCUAAACCAAAAUUGCUAAGUUCCAAAAAUGUUGGAUACAUCGGGUGCUUAUUUGUAAAAGUAUCUAAAUGAAAGUGGGCCCUUAAAGAGUGUGUCAUGAACCAAGGAUUAUAAUUAACCCCAUUAUGGGGGCACAAGGUCAAAUAUAAGAGGAAAAAACAAAGUCAGUUGUACAAAUGGAAAAAGUGCAAAUGAAAAAUGAUGACCUUUAACAAGGCAAGGACAGUAAGAAUAAGAAAAUACUGGAUUGCCUCUCAUUCUCUGAAAAAUCCUAAUGAAUAUCAGAUGUAGUGAUUUUCUACCUUCCCCAAUUUAUUUCACUCUCCUCCCACAGCUGAUAAAUAAUCUAUGAAAUACAGUUGUCCUGCCCCUUAUUUUACUUGUCAUUAUUUGUUUUCAUUUAUUUUGACUGGGUUAAUGCACUAAUGGCUCAUUUAUCUACGAUGAUCAAAAUUUGGUUGCAAAGACAGCCCUAAAGUAACACCUAUUUGCCUUCUACCGUUCUCUCACUGGUCUCUGGAUGUUAGAAUUGCUGGUGCAUUUUAAACAACAGACAUUCUUAAUGGAUAGCUGUUUUGUGGGAAGCUUUUCCCUUCCCCUGGAACUUAAUGCGUGAUUUCCCAGAGAGCUGAAACAUACGAUUCUGGGAAUUCUCUUGUUCCCUGACAUAAUAAAGAGUGAUUGUGAGUGGGAAGAACUUUAUGGGGGUCAGUCAUAAAUGCCGUCAGUAAGCGUGCCUCACCUAUUCUACGCAGCACAGGAAGUUUGCGGAGAGGACGCUUGAACUGAAUAAUCCACGCUGGAGCUCUCAGAUCACUAGAUGGAAAGUCAGAGGUCAAACACCCUUACAUGGACGUGCUGAAGCCAUCAAAAAACAAAACAGAAAAAAACCUCUAGGAAAUGAUCUAGGAAAAUGCCAACAGAAUCCUGGAUUUGAGUCUGUCCUUUGAAAGCAUCUCUGCUAGAGUUCCCACUUCCAAACCCCUUUCAGCUCUUCGGGAUUCAGCCUCCAGGUUGCCCUCGGAGUGGAGUCUGUGGCUUUCCACCGGAGCAGCGCCCAGGAAGUGUUUUCGUGUGAUGAAAGUUAUUUUUCAGUGCUGUACAAGCGUCUUGAAUUACUCUGGUAGCUUUUCCAGAAAGACCCAUGACUUCACCACAUUUCUCGAGUUACGAUGAAGGUCCUCUGGAUGUCAGCAUGGCAGCCACAAACCUGGAGAACCAGCUGCACAGCGCACAGAAGAACCUCCUGUUCCUUCAGCGGGAGCAUGCCAGCACGCUCAAGGGGCUGCACUCCGAGAUCAGGCGGCUGCAGCAGCACUGCACAGAUUUAACAUAUGAGCUGACAGUCAAAAGUUCGGAACAGACAGGAGACGGGACUUCUAAAAGCAGUGAAUUAAAGAAAAGAUGUGAAGAGCUGGAAGCCCAACUGAAAGUGAAAGAGAACGAAAAUGCUGAGUUGUUGAAAGAACUGGAGCAGAAAAACGCGAUGAUCACAGUGCUGGAGAACACCAUCAAGGAGCGAGAGAAGAAGUACCUGGAGGAGCUGAAGGCCAAGAGUCACAAGCUGACCCUGCUGUCUAGCGAGCUGGAGCAGCGGGCCAGCACCAUCGCCUACCUGACCUCCCAGCUGCACGCCGCCAAGAAGAAGCUCAUGAGCUCCAGCGGGACCUCAGAUGCCAGCCCGUCAGGGAGCCCCGUGCUGGCCAGCUACAAGCCAGCGCCCCCCAAAGACAAGCUACCCGAAACGCCUCGCCGCCGCAUGAAAAAGAGCCUCUCAGCCCCCUUGCACCCGGAAUUUGAAGAGGUCUACAGAUUCGGGGCAGAGAGCAGGAAACUCCUUUUGCGGGAACCAGUGGAUGCUAUGCCCGACCCCACCCCAUUUCUGCUGGCUAGGGAGUCCGCCGAGGUCCACCUCAUCAAAGAGAGGCCCCUCGUCAUCCCCCCCAUCGCCUCCGACCGAAGCGGCGAGCAGCACAGCCCGGCCCGCGAAAAGCCGCACAAGGCCCACGUCGGGGUGGCACAUCGGAUCCACCACGCCACCCCGCCGCAGGCCCAGCCCGAGGUGAAGACCCUGGCGGUCGACCAGGUGAACGGAGGCAAGGUGGUGAGGAAGCACUCAGGGACGGACAGAACUGUGUGAAGCCCGCCGUGCCCCACCCCGCGCUGUCCAUGCACUGUGAGCACCACUGGGAAAUCUCAGCCACACCUUUUCUGUUUAAUCCCAUGCAUGCCAAACACUUUUCACACCUACCGACCCAUUCUCCUUCUGCUUCUCUUGCCCUCUUCUUCACACCAAAAUAUGAUCGUGUCCCUGCCGCAGAAUAUGUAUUUCCUAAUUGCUGUGGCCAAACGCCUGUGUGCCGAAUCGCUUGCUUCUGAUCCCGCUCCGUGUAACCUAAGUGCGCUGCAGGCAAAGCCCAGGCCACGGCUGCGUCACUACUGAUGUUCACGAUGCCACACAGUCACACACCUAAUUCAUUCUCAAGUCGGAGCAACACAUACCAACCUUGACCUUAUCCUCAAGCUCCAGGGCAGCCUGGCCGAGCAGCCCCUGCUCCCUCCUGGAGACCCUUGUCACCUCCCGAGCUCCUCCUGGAGACCCCUGUCACCUCCUGACCAACCUUUCCCAGGGCGGCACCGAUCACCGAGCAGCCGUGCGUGUAUCUCAAGGAACUAAAUAAGAUGACGCUACUCCUCAUAGCACCACAACCUGAAUGUGUGUUCAUAUUUUUUUGUUAGUUUUAUCCAAAAUGUUUAAGAUCCCAACAAACUUUAUUUUCUAAACCUGCCUUCCUUCUGUUUUGUGUCUUUUAUUAAACAAACACCUGAAGGAGGGCUAGGAGACUGCAGGAGGGAGAGCAAUCACAGGUCCCAGAAGCGACUCCGGCCUCCUCCCGGCCCAGAGCUAGUCCUUAGAAUGUGCUGCGCUCCUGAGCUUCUGUGGGAAGCUGCUUUUGCCUCUGAUGGCCCCUGCCCACUGUGCUGCCCGUGCUAGCCCCUCUCCUCCCUCAUGGAGUGAAGCCACCCCUCACCUCCAGGUGGCCAGCCAGGGCUCCAGGCCAGCCUCAUGGUGCACAGAGGGAAGGGGUGCCCAGUGACCACUGGUCCUGGAGGUUCUGUGUCCUUACCUGACCCCACACAGACCCAGGCAGGCUGGGGGUAGAAGCUCAUGCAGGAACUAAACACUAAGCUCAACAACUUCACAGUCGCCGUAGCAGGUCAGAGCCAAAGAAGCUAGGGCCAGAGAGUUCUGGAAGGGGGAGAAGUGGCUCCAGGUGACUGGUCACUUCUGCUCUGUGCCCGACAUCAUCAGCCCUUCUUGCCAAAAAGGAGCAUCUGCUGAAACAGACCUGGAUCAUCGAAAACACACCUUUGGAAAUUACAUUAGGAUUCUCACUUGUGCCAAUGCUAUGUAUGCCAGGCACUUUUGCCUAAUCAAGUGUUUUCUCUGAGAAGGAAAAGAAAACUCCACACAUCUUAAAAUACUCUCCAAUAUUUACUUUUUGAUUAUAUAAAUUCCUUUUAAAAAGUAGUAUUAAAAACAAAACCAUUCAGGUUAAUUUGUAUGGAAA